GCAGUUGGCGGUCGGGCUAGAGAAGAGAGGCGCCUGCGCUUGCGAGCUGGGCUUGUGAGUGGGGCUGCCGAGAGGGCAGGCGUGGGGCGAGGCCAAAGGACUGAACCCGCAGGAGCGUCACGGGCGCCGGGGCGGCUGCCGACGGCGGGACUGGGUCAGUGAGAAGCCCGUGGGCCCCCGCCCUGCCUGCUACUCCCAUCCCCACCUGCGCGCUCCCCAUGGGGGACGACCCCCGAUUGGGUCCGAUGCCUACCCUCGGGGUGGAGCCGGCAGGUUUUCUAUCAGAUGUUCCACGUAAUAAUGCUGGAGUUAAGAAGUUUCCAUUAUUUUGCUCCAAACCAGAAGACUCUGUUCCCUGUAUAUAGAAUAGGAGUAAUAUUUGAAAACAACUGGCUGAUGUUUAAAACUGAAGAUUGUCAUGAUUGUUUAUCCUAAUCCCAAUGCUGAAGUAAGAUUGUCUUGGAAAUACUAAGUUGGGGUAAUCCAAAUCUAUUUCUGGAACCAUGAAAAUUUUGCUAGUUUUUGACUUUGACAAUACAAUCAUAGAUGACAAUAGUGACACUUGGAUUGUACAAUGUGCUCCCAACAAAAAGCUUCCUAUUGAACUACGUGAUUCUUAUCGAAAAGGAUUUUGGACAGAAUUUAUGGGCAGAGUCUUUAAGUAUUUGGGAGAUAAGGGUGUAAGAGAACAUGAAAUGAAAAGAGCAGUGACAUCAUUGCCUUUCACUCCAGGGAUGGUGGAACUCUUCAACUUUAUAAGAAAGAAUAAGGAUAAAUUUGACUGCAUUAUUAUUUCAGAUUCAAAUUCGGUCUUCAUAGAUUGGGUUUUAGAAGCUGCCAGUUUUCAUGACAUAUUUGAUAAAGUGUUUACAAAUCCAGCAGCUUUUAAUAGCAAUGGUCAUCUCACUGUUGAAAAUUAUCAUACUCAUUCUUGCAAUAGAUGCCCAAAGAAUCUUUGCAAAAAGGUAGUUUUGAUAGAAUUUGUAGAUAAACAGUUACAACAGGGAGUGAAUUAUACACAAAUUGUUUAUAUUGGUGAUGGUGGAAAUGAUGUCUGUCCAGUCACCUUUUUAAAGAAUGAUGAUGUUGCCAUGCCACGGAAAGGAUAUACCUUACAGAAAACUCUUUCCAGAAUGUCUCAAAAUCUUGAGCCUAUGGAAUAUUCUGUUGUAGUUUGGUCCUCAGGUGUUGAUAUAAUUUCUCAUUUACAAUUUCUAAUAAAGGAUUAAUAUGUCAGCAA